AACUUCUCCAGCCGGCCGGGGCGAGCGCCAGCGCGGCGUCCGGGGCGAGUGACACGCAGAGCUGAAGCCAUGGUUCAUCAGGUGCUCUACCGGGCGCUGGUCUCCACCAAGUGGCUGGCGGAGUCCAUCAGGACUGGCAAGCUGGGGCCCGGCCUGCGGGUGCUGGACGCGUCCUGGUACUCACCAGGCACCCGAGAGGCCCGCAAGGAGUACCUCGAGCGCCACGUACCCGGCGCCUCUUUCUUUGACAUAGAAGAGUGCCGGGACACGGCGUCGCCCUACGAGAUGAUGCUGCCCAGCGAGGCUGGCUUCGCCGAGUAUGUGGGCCGCCUGGGCAUCAGCAACCACACGCACGUGGUGGUGUAUGAUGGUGAACACCUGGGCAGCUUCUAUGCUCCCCGGGUCUGGUGGAUGUUCCGUGUGUUUGGCCACCGCACCGUAUCAGUGCUCAAUGGUGGCUUCCGGAACUGGCUGAAGGAGGGCCACCCGGUGACAUCCGAGCCCUCACGCCCAGAACCGGCCGUCUUCAAAGCCACACUGGACCGCUCCCUGCUCAAGACCUACGAGCAGGUGCUGGAGAACCUUGAAUCUAAGAGGUUCCAGCUGGUGGAUUCAAGGUCUCAAGGGCGGUUCCUGGGCACCGAGCCGGAGCCGGAUGCAGUAGGACUGGACUCGGGCCAUAUCCGUGGUGCCGUCAACAUGCCUUUCAUGGACUUCCUGACUGAGGAUGGCUUCGAGAAGGGCCCAGAAGAGCUCCGUGCUCUGUUCCAGACCAAGAAGGUGGAUCUCUCGCAGCCUCUCAUUGCCACGUGCCGCAAGGGAGUCACCGCCUGCCACGUGGCCUUGGCUGCCUACCUCUGCGGCAAGCCUGAUGUGGCCGUGUACGAUGGCUCCUGGUCCGAGUGGUUUCGCCGGGCCCCCCCAGAGAGCCGUGUGUCCCAGGGAAAGUCUGAGAAGGCCUGAGCCGUGACCUCUUCUGCUUACUGUAACUGCGGCCGGUUUAGUGACCCCAUGACUUACAGCCGGUUCUUACCUCUUAGGUGAAGGAGAUGACAUGUUUUUAGAAUUGCUGUGCAAGGCUCACCCUCUCUCUGUCAACACUGGAAUAAACUUUGCCUUUUCUGA